AACAGUUACUUUUUGAGCCUUGCGUUGUUGGAAGUAGGCUAGGGGACUUGAGGAGAGUGAUGAAAAUGUUCCACAUAUUGUGGGGAAUGGAGAAGAGAAGUGUUUCAAGAUAAAUAAGUGAAAGAAUUGCUGAGCAGCAUCAGAGGCUCAUCUGAGAUUGGAACUCAUAAAUUUGUAAUCAGCAUAUUUUACUGUUUUUUCUGGCAGUGUUCUGCAAGCAGGAGAAAAGCAAAGACACACUGUAUUGAAGGUGGAUGAGGGAGGAGAGAUGCAAGGGAGAUGAAGUAAUGGGGAUGUAGGCUAAGUAAUGAAGUUAGUAAAGUAGAGCAGGGCUAAGAUAGCCAACCAGUGGUGAGAGAUGCAAGGGUAAUGCCAAGGAGUGAUUAAUUAAAAUACUAAUUUAUUGUUUGUUUGAGGUUAUAGUAAUCAUAAACCCUGUAUUUACUUUUCCCUUAAACUAACAUUUAAUAUUUUUAUUUGUAAACUAUUUACUGACUUAUUGCAGAUGUUUCUUAGCUAUUUUGCUUUAUUUUCCCUAAAAUGAAAAUUCCUUGAAAGCAUCAUCUUUGUUACUUAAUAAGUAUCUAAUAGUUUAUAUAUUUGAGACAUAUUUAUUCUUCAGUACCUCUGAAUGAGAGAUUUUAAGAUUAUCUUGCUAAUAUUUUUGGCUGGGACACCAAGAAGAGAAUACCAGUGUCUAAUAUGGUUCAUUUUGACUGACAAAAAUUUCACUAGUAAUACAAUCGUAUCAGUGGCCCAAAGGAGUAAGAAAGCAUCCAAGCUAUUUUUUGUUGUUGUUGGAAUUUUUACAUGCUAGAGACAGAUUUUAUCUUAGUAUAGUUUAUUCAUAUUCCAGGCCUGUGACCCUUAAUCAAUUUUUUUUUUCUUUUGAGAUGGAGUCUGGCUCUGUUGCUAAGCUGGAGUGCAGUGGUAUAAUCACGGCUCACUGCAACCUCCCCGUUCUGUGUUCAAGCGAUUGCUCUGCCUCAGCCUCCCGAGUAGCUGGGACUACAGGCGUGCACCACCAUGCCCGGCUAACUUUUUGUAUUUUAGUAGAGACAGGGUUUUACCAUGUUGGCCAUGAUGGUCUGGAUAUCCUGUCCUUGUGACCUGCCUGCCUCAGCCUCCCAAAGUGCUGGGAUUACAGGCAUGAGCCACCGUGCCCGGCCUCCCCUUAAUUUUAAUGGCUGCUAUAAUGUUAUAAUUCUCUGAGUGCUGGGGAAAAAAAGACAUUGCUUUUAUUUGGAAUAAUAUCUAGACUUAAAAAGUAUAUAUUUUAUGAGGAUAUUUAUGAUUUUUCUUCCUGAUAAAGAUAUCACAUGAAAUAGCAUUUGUUUUAUAAGCCAUUUAAAAAUAUUUAAAUUUAACAUUACAAAUUGUUAUAAUUUUUAUCCUCCUAGUCAAUAUUAUUUCUUAUUGUUUCUUGUCACUAAAUAAAAAGUAAAUAAGCAACUUUAGGAAGCGCAUGCAUUCAGAGUUUCCUGCAAAGCACAGGGUUUCAUAAAUGCCAUAUGAGGAUGUAAAGAAAAAGAAAAUUAGAUUACUACAACUUUGUUCUUAUUUUCUGGGUUCCUUAAGCCUCUUCCAUACUUCUUUAAUGCUCAAGAGGACUAUAGAAGUACUUAUUUAUAUGACAGCCCCAAUGUUAGUAUUUCUUGAGAUUAUGUUUAAAUUGUACCUUCAAUAUUGAGAUUUUUGUGAGCAAUAAUAUGUGAUACGCAUUUUAAAAAAAUUUAAAGAUUUUUAAAAAUUAUGAUUAAACUAGAUUUUGUCAAAUGAUAAAUAGUGUAGAAGUAUAUUGCUAUUUGUGUAUAGGUAGUAUGAAAAACUUACAUUUGCCAGAAAUUGGCUUUUACAUUUCAAAAAUGUUGUGGAAAGUACUUCUUAGAACAUGAGAUAUUUGAUGUAUUUUGUAGGCAAACAGCAAGAAACCAACUGAAGGAUGAGAUUAAAUAGGAACAAGAAAAGGUGGUGGAGAAAGGAGGGGGCAGAGUUUUUACUAUGGUAACAUAAACUCCUGAGUUCUGUCAAACUGAUCUUUGGUAGGACAUUACAGUGUGGUUAAGUUUUUCUUGCAUAUUAUCAGUACUUGUAAAUUUGGAGAAAUGAAAUUUGAGAUUUUUUUGUUUGCUUUUAAAAAAACAGCAGUCAGUUGUGGACUUUUAAAAAAAUUAGGUCCAAAAUUGUAUCAAAAUUAUGUCAAAAAAGCUCUGUCCAGCUCCAGUGUUAAAAAGAAAUUCCACUUUAUCCAUGUUUUCUCAAAUUAUAAAUAGACUUUUUUUAAAAAAGUUCAUUUAUAAGUCAAUUAUAUGGGGCCAGGCGCGGUGGCUCACGCCUGUAAUGCCAGCACUUUGGGAGGCCGAGGUGGGCGAAUCACCUGAGGUCGGGAGUUUGAGACCAGUCUGGCCAACAUGGUGAAACUUCGUCUCUACUGAAAAUACGAAAAUUAGGCAGGCAAGGUGACAGGCGUUUGUAGUCCCAUUUUCUUGGGAGGCUGAGGUAGGAGAAUCAGUUGAAUCCAGAAGCAGGAAGUUGCAGUGAGCCGAGAUCACGCCACUGCACUCCAGCCUGAGUGACAGAGCGAGACUGUCUCAAAAAAAAAAAAAAGGGUCAAUUAUAUGGAAUUCAGAAGUUGUUGUUGUUGAAAUGGCCUCUCUCCACUGCCUUGGUCAGAGUGCAGUGAUGCCAUCACAGCUCACUGCAGCCUCAACUUCUUGGGCUCAAACUUUCUUGAAAGUGCUAAAAUGAUGCGCCAAAGUAGUAUAUUUAUCCCACGUUACAGGUGCACAAUUACUCCUUUGGUAAGAAAAAUGCAGUAAAUUACACUGAUGAAAAUGUAGGCUGGGCAUGGUGGCUCACGCCUGUAAUCCCAGCACUUUGGGAGGCUGAGGCAGGCGGAUCACCUGAGGUCAGGAGUUUGAGACCAGCCUGGGCAACAUGGUGAAACCCUGUCUAUACUAAAAAUACAAAGAUUAGCCGGGUGUGGUGCUGGGUGCCAGUAGUCUUAGCUACUCAGGAGGCUGAGGCAGGAGAAUCGCUUGAACCCGGGAGGCGGAGGUUGUUAUGAACUGAGAUCUUGCCACUGUACUCCAGUCUAGGCGACACAGCGAGACUCCAUCUCAAAAAAAAAGAAAAGAAAAUGUAUAGUAUCUUUUUUCUUUUGGAAUAGUCCUGGUCUUAUAAAAUUGUCACAAUUAGAUGUUAAUUAUUUCUAUCAUUCAAUAGAAGAUGAACAUAAGUAACAGUUAUGAGAGUAAAUAAUUAUUGAUUCAGUCAUUGAUCUGAUAAGGAGACAAAGACAGAAGAGGAAAGCACCAGGAGCCUGAAAUGGGUGGGAAGGAGUAGUGACAUAAUUUAAAAUUUUUUUAUUGGUGCAGAGACAGAGGCAUGAAACUUAGAAUCAGAAAAUCUGAAUUCAGAUUCCCUCUUCACAGUUAACUCACUGAAUGGUCUGAAAUCAAGUUACUCUAGAACUUGUUUCUUCAUUCAUAUAAUGGAGAUCGUUGAUUCAUUGAUUCAUUCAGAAAUAUUUUUCUUACUAGGUUAUUUUGAAGAUGAACAAAAACAUCUGAAAGUAAGCUAUUAUGAACUGUAUAGUGUUCACUGUAUUUGACUGUAUAGUCAGAUAUUAGUGAUGAUGCAAUUCUUCUUGUCUUUCCAUUUCAUUCUUCCCUGUCAUCCUUCCUUCUUUCAUUGAUAGCGUAUUUUUACAUGCUCUUGAUCUAGCGCUUCACAGAACCUUCAGAGCCUGCAGUCCCAGCUGAUUUCCACUCCUCCUCCCACUCACACAUUGGGCACAGGAGUAGGGUGUGAGGCAACUUUUCUAGGUCAGCCUGCUUAUUUUCUCACUGUUGACUGACAAAGUCCUGUCUUUCUCAAGGUGUGACAUAAACCUGAGGUGCCUUUUAGUCCCUGGGCUUGAUAUUCUUUCUUUCUCACUUUGCCUCUCCUUUUCCCAUCCCCUCUCGCCCCAUUCCUGUGUGUAUGUAACUCUGACCAUCUCCUUUCUCCACCACUUACUUGUUCCUUUUUUUUUUUUUUGAGACGGAGUCGCGCUCUGUCACCCAGGCUGGAGUUCAAUGGCAUGAUCUUGGCUCAUUGCAACCUCUGCCUCCCAGGUCCAAGCGAUUCUUGUGCCUCAACCUUCUGAGUAGCUGGGAUUACAGGUGCAUGCCACCAUGCCCGGCUAAUUUUUCGUAUUUUUUGUAGAGAUGGGGUUUCACCACGUUGGCUAGGCUGAUCUUGAACUCCUGACCUCAGGUGAUCUAACCACCUCGUCCUCCCAAAGUGCUGGAAUUACAGACAUGAGCCACUGCGCCCGGCCUCUUGUUCCUCUUUAAUCUCACCCUUCAAUUGGCUUCUUGCUGUUUGCCUACAAAUAUGGUCAGGUCUCCGAUAGCCUAAAAGAUUCUUGCUCAACUCUUGUUCUUUUUUUUUUUUUCCUUUUACCACCAAAGAGAUGUUGAUAUUGUUGCCUUUAUUACUUCAUCACUUACCUCUUAACCUCAGUGGGAUUGCUUCUUCCCUAACCACUGUCCUGAAACUGUUCUUAAUCCAGUAUCCUUUCUAAAGUUAGUAAUCUCCUUGAUCUCUUUGCAGCAUGUUGAUGCUACUUACUGUUCGCACUUUACUUCCUGACACAUCUUCCCUGUGUAAGGAUGGUAUUUCUGAUUGCCUUUGUCUUUUCCUCUAAACAUAUUUGCCCUACCCCUUCUUCAGAGCUUUCAUUAGCUCUCUUCUUCGGCACUUUCUCCAUUUGUAAUAUCACUUUCCUGUGACUAUCUGUAGUUAUCUACUAAUUCAUUCCUGUAAUGUAAUUGAACUAGAAGCAGUAAUGGAAAAUUCAGGGAAGCAGGAUUCUGUUCACUACAAGAAUAUUUUUUCUCCAAAGUAAUUAUGGUUGUUUUACAGUAGUACUCUGCUUUUAAAGUAGUUAAUUCUUCAUUAUUGAAGUUUUCAAGUAGAGGCAAAAAGACACCUUGUAGAAAGGAUUUAUAUAUGAAGUAGAAAGUCAAGCCAGAUAUUCUUUUAAAGUCUUGUCCAACUCAAAAAUUGUAAUUUUUAUCUCGUCUACUCUACUUCCAUGGACUUAACUUUGACCUAUGCUCAGAUGUCUUCCAAACCAUUAUUUCCAGUCACUCCCCUACCACCUCCUCGUCUGUCUUCUCUCCCACGGGCACAAUUUUGUCAUCAAAGUUGCUUAUGUUCUAGGCCACCAUAUUUUCUAGCUUCAUUAUCACUUUCCAAUAUUCUUUUUACCCCCUUUAGUGGCAAGGCAAUGAGGAUCAUUUUUCUAUGCUUUGGUGACUUUUCUGAAAGUAAGUUAUGUCUGCCCAUAUUGGUUUAGUUUGUUAUUGCUGUUUUCCCUCUACUUUCUCCUACCCACCACCUCUCUCUCCAGGAUUAGGAAUGCUCAAGCAAAGAAAAGGACGCCAGAAGAGGAGGCUCAGGAUCCUAAAGUUUGCAUUUAUUUUAAAAUUUUGCAUGGCACAGUUGAAAUGUUAAUGUUUGCUGACCAUUUAAAAAGUAAGAUGUUUGCCGGGCGUGGUGGCUCACGCCUGUAAUCCCAGCACUUUGGGAGGCCAAGGCGGGUGGAUCACCUGAGGUCAGGAGUUCAAGACUAGCCUGACCAAUAUGGCGAAACCCUGUCUCUACUAAAAUUACAGAAAUUAGCUGGGCGUGGUGGCAUGCGCCUGUAGUCCCAGAUACUCAGGAGGCUGAGGCAGGAGAAUGGCUUGAAACUGGGAGGCGGAGGUUGCAGUGAAGCCGCGAUUGCACCACUGCACUCUAGCCUGCUGACAGUGAGACUGUCUCAAAAAAAAAAAGUUUAUAAUAAUAGUUGUUGCAAUUAUUUAUUGAAUGUCUACUAUGUACCAAGUAUUAUGCUAUGAACUCACAUAAGUUAUUUCAUUUAAAUCUUAUGACAUUCCUAUGAGGAAGAUACUGCUGCUGUCCCAUUUUACAAAUUAGGAAACAGACUUAGGAAGGUAAGACAGUUGUCACACAACUAAUAAAUGACAGUGAUCUAACUGAUUGUAUGGCCAAUACUCUUAACUAGUAUAUCGUUUUACAAGGAAGGUGGAGAUCUAGAAUCAAAUUUCAGAAAGUCAAGUAAUGUUAAUACAAACAAGGAAAUAUAUUUUGGAUUUAUAUUUUUAGAUUAUUUGAAAUGUAUGUGAACCUUUUGAGGUAUUGUGUUAGUGGCUUGUGUGUCUUACACACUUUCUGUGAUAUUCAUUCAUUUGCUCAUUCGUUCAUUGAAUAGUCAUGCAGUUUAUUGAAUGCUUAGACUUUGUAUUGGGUGUGGUAUAGGAAAGUGAAUGAAACAAAUAUAAGUAAGUAAGUUUACAGUAUAGUGGGAGAGAUAGGAAACAAGCAGGUAAAUAAUCACAUAAUUUAUUUUAGUCUAGAGUAGUUUCCCACCUUUUUAAAAUGACUGAGUAUCCAAGCCAUUUUCUUAAUAGACUAUCUCAUACUCUUAAUUUGUCUCAUUGUUUCCUCAUAUAUGGUGGUUUAAACCUUACUAUCCUACUUCCUUCUAUUUACUGUAAACUCAAAGGUAGGUCUAGAGCAAGGGUGCUGAACCUUGAGUUCACAGACUCUUGUAGGGUCUGUAGAAUUCAGGGAAUCUGUGAACUUUAGAUGGGGAAAAAAUUACAUCUUUAUUUUAACUUAUUCCCUAACUCAGUGGUUCUCAACCGGGGUGAGUUUGUCUUCUCCUUCCCCAACCCUAGGACAUUUUUGAUUGUCACAGCUGGGUGGGUACAAGAUAGUCCCUGAUAACAGAAUUAUCCCUUUCAAAAUGUCAGUAGUGUCAAAGUUGAAAAACUCUGCCCUAACUGGAUUUUAGCAUUUCCUUUAAUUAGGAAUAUAAGAAACGCUUCAUGGAUACAGUAUGGACAGUACAUUUACAGUACCUGUAGCUUUGUCACCAAUAGAAAUCUCAGGUAUUCUCAUAUCACAUUCAAUUGCUACAGAUAUCUUAAGAUUUAAUUUAUGCUCAUUUAUUGCCUAUAAGGUAGUUACUAGAUUCGUAUUAAGAAGCAAUAGUAGGCUGGGCGCGGUGGCUCACGCCUGUAAUCCCAGCACUUUGGGAGGCCGAGGCGGGCGGAUCACAAGGUCAGGAGAUCGAGACCAUCUUGGCUAACACGGUGAAACCCCGUCUCUACUAAAAAUACAAAAAAUUAGCCGGGCGCGGUGGCGGGCACCUGUAGUCCCAGCUACUCGGGAGGCUGAGGCAGGAGAAUGGCGUGAACCUGGGAGGCGGAGCUUGCAGUGAGCCGAGAUUGUGCCACUGCAAUCUGGCCUGGGCUAAAGAGCGGGACUCCGUCUCAAAAAAAAAAAAAAAAAAAAAAAAAAAAAAAAGAAGCAAUAGUAGACUGGGCAUGGUAGCUCAUGCCUGUAAUACCAGCACUCUGGGAGGCUGAUGUGGGAGGACUGCCUGAGCCCAGGAGUUCAGGACCAGCCUGGACAACAUAGUGAGACCUCGUCUCUACAAAAAUACAAAAAUUAGCCAGGUGUGGUAGUGUGCACCUGUGGUCCCAGCUACUCAGGAGGCUGAGGUGGGAGGAUCGCUUGCACCCAGGAGGUUGAGAUUGCAGUGAGCUGUGAUUAUGUCACUGCACUCCAGCCUGGGUGACAGUGAGAGCCUGUCUCAAAAAGAAGAAAUAAUACUAUGUUAUAAUUUAAACAGUUAUUAUUGUAGCUGUAGUUCAGUAUAAUUGUCCAUUGUAGUGUUGUGUGUUUUAUGCAUUUAAAAACAUUAUUCUAAGAAGGUAUCCAUAAACUUCGCCAGACUGUAAAAGAAAUCCACAGGACAAUAAAGCUUAACUCCUGAUCUAGAGAUUGGAUUGGAUUGGAUUGGAUUAAACAUUUUUGAAGAGACUAUUUCAUAGUUGAGUGGUGAUUUUAUGCAAUGGCUUCAAGCCACAGUUCUUCACCAGUGCCUCAAGGAAGCAGCAGUGAUGUUUUCUUUAAAAUAGAGGUAGAUCCGUCAAAACACAUUCGACCUGUGCCAUCACUGCCAGAUGUGUGUCCCAAGGAACCCACAGUUACAGAUCAACAUAGAUGGACUGUAUAUCAUUCCAAAGUAAAUCUCCCAGCAGCAUUAAACGAUCCUAGAUUAGCAAAAAGAGAAUCUGACUUCUUCACAAAAACAUGGGGAUUGGACUUUGUGGACACUGAAGUCAUACCUUCAUUCUACCUCCCACAGAUCAGCAAGGAACAUUUUACAGUAUAUCAACAGGAAAUCUCUCAGAGAGAGAAGAUUCAUGAGAGAUGCAAGAAUAUUUGUCCUCCUAAAGAUACCUUCGAAAGGACUCUUUUACAUACUCAUGAUAAAUCCAGGACAGAUCUGGAGCAAGUACCUAAGAUUUUUAUGAAACCAGAUUUUGCCUUGGAUGAUUCCUUAACUUUUAAUUCAGUUUUACCAUGGUCUCAUUUUAAUACUGCUGGUGGAAAAGGAAAUCGUGAUGCAGCUUCCUCAAAGUUGCUUCAAGAAAAGCUGAGCCAUUAUCUGGAUAUUGUGGAAGUAAACAUUGCUCACCAGAUCUCUCUACGUUCAGAAGCAUUUUUUCAUGCAAUGACCUCUCAACACGAGUUGCAGGACUACCUCAGGAAAACUUCCCAGGCUGUAAAAAUGCUUCGAGAUAAAAUUGCACAGAUUGAUAAAGUAAUGUGUGAAGGAUCACUCCACAUUUUAAGACUGGCACUUACCAGAAAUAAUUGUGUUAAAGUAUACAAUAAGCUGAAGUUAAUGGCCACUGUACACCAGACUCAGCCUACAGUACAGGUGUUAUUAUCUACUUCUGAAUUUGUUGGAGCAUUGGACUUAAUAGCAACAACACAAGAGGUUCUACAGCAGGAACUUCAGGGCAUUCACAGUUUCCGGCAUUUGGGAUCACAGCUUUGUGAAUUAGAAAAACUGAUAGAUAAAAUGAUGAUUGCAGAAUUUUCUACUUAUUCUCACAGUGACUUAAAUAGACCACUGGAAGAUGACUGUCAAGUUUUAGAAGAGGAAAGACUAAUAUCUCUUGUAUUUGGACUUUUAAAACAAAGAAAGCUUAAUUUUUUAGAAAUCUAUGGUGAAAAAAUGGUUAUUACAGCAAAGAAUAUCAUUAAACAGUGUGUGAUUAAUAAAGUUUCACAAACAGAAGAAAUAGACACAGAUGUUGUUGUGAAGCUUGCAGAUCAGAUGAGAAUGUUGAAUUUUCCCCAGUGGUUUGAUCUGCUCAAGGAUAUUUUCUCUAAGUUUACAAUUUUCCUACAGAGAGUGAAGGCAACAUUAAAUAUCAUUCACAGUGUUGUUCUCUCAGUUCUUGACAAAAACCAAAGGACUAGAGAAUUGGAAGAGAUUUCACAACAGAAGAAUGCUGCAAAAGAUAAUUCACUGGACACAGAGGUGGCUUAUUUAAUCCAUGAAGGCAUGUUUAUAAGUGAUGCAUUCGGUGAGGGUGAGCUAACACCUAUAGCAGUUGACACUACCUCUCAAAGAAAUGCAUCUCCAAAUAGUGAGCCCUGCAGCAGUGAUUCUGUAUCCGAGCCAGAAUGUACUACUGAUUCUUCAUCCAGCAAAGAGCACACAUCAUCAUCUGCUAUUCCAGGAGGUGUGGAUAUUAUGGUCAGUGAAGAUAUGAAAUUAACUGACUCAGAGCUAGGAAAGCUGGCAAAUAAUAUCCAGGAAUUAUUAUAUAGUGCCUCAGAUAUAUGCCAUGAUCGAGCUGUCAAAUUUCUCAUGUCAAGAGCAAAGGAUGGUUUUCUUGAGAAGCUAAAUUCCAUGGAAUUCAUAACACUUUCUAGAUUAAUGGAAACAUUCAUUUUAGACACCGAACAGAUCUGUGGAAGAAAAAGCACGUCAUUACUUGGAGCACUUCAGAGCCAAGCUAUUAAGUUUGUAAAUAGGUUUCAUGAAGAGAGAAAAACCAAGCUCAGCCUCCUCUUAGACAAUGAGCGCUGGAAGCAAGCAGAUGUUCCUGCAGAAUUUCAGGAUCUUGUUGAUUCUCUGUCAGAUGGGAAGAUUGCUUUACCUGAAAAAAAAUCAGGAGCCACAGAAGAAAGGAAACCAGCUGAAGUUCUUAUUGUCGAGGGACAACAGUAUGCAGUUGUUGGAACCGUAUUGCUGUUAAUAAGAAUUAUCCUUGAAUAUUGCCAGUGUGUGGAUAACAUCCCAUCUGUUACUACUGACAUGCUUACUCGUCUGUCAGAUUUAUUGAAGUACUUCAAUUCAAGAAGUUGCCAGUUAGUUCUUGGAGCUGGUGCACUGCAAGUUGUUGGACUAAAAACGAUAACUACAAAAAAUUUGGCUCUUUCUUCACGAUGUUUGCAGUUAAUUGUGCACUACAUUCCUGUGAUCCGGGCUCAUUUUGAAGCUCGACUACCACCUAAGCAAUAUAGCAUGCUUAGGCAUUUUGAUCAUAUCACUAAGGACUACCAUGAUCACAUAGCUGAAAUAUCAGCUAAGCUUGUAGCGAUAAUGGAUAGCUUAUUUGACAAGCUGUUAUCUAAGUAUGAAGUGAAGGCUCCUGUUCCUUCUGCCUGUUUCAGGAAUAUUUGUAAGCAAAUGACAAAAAUGCACGAAGCUAUAUUUGAUCUCCUUCCAGAAGAACAAACACAGAUGUUAUUUUUAAGAAUUAAUGCAAGUUAUAAACUCCACUUGAAAAAGCAGUUAUCUCACUUAAAUGUGAUAAAUGAUGGAGGACCUCAAAAUGGGUUGGUCACAGCAGAUGUAGCUUUUUACACUGGAAAUCUUCAAGCCUUAAAAGGCCUUAAAGAUUUGGACCUAAAUAUGGCCGAAAUUUGGGAGCAGAAGAGGUGAUGUCAUCCUGGAAAACUGGGUAGUUCAUCUGACCAUGGGAUGUGUUUGUUAUGAAGAAAAUCUGGAUGCCUGUGAUUCGAGAAUUGAACCUGAAACCCAAAGUGAACUGGGGUGGGGGAAGGGAAAAAGGAAAGUAUCAAGUGUUGGGAAACUGGAUUCAGUGGGAUCUACAAGGAAUGUCAUUUUUGUGCAUCCUACAGUGAGGAGUAACUGAUCAGGUGUCUAUAACAUUUUUCAUUCUCUCUGGAAACAGACUCAGGUUUCUUUGGACCAAAUCCAAAAGAACACAUAGCUGUAACACAGCUGUAGUUGACUAGAAUGCUCUGUAUACUUUAUAUUAAAAAAUGCUUUGCAUUUCUUCCAGUGCAAUGAAAUUCAUAUGGUGUCCCACCUUAUUUAAUGAUGGUACAAUUUAAAAUCUUAGUCAACUUCUGUAGAAAGUUUUCUCUAUGAAAGUAAAGCUGUUUGAAAAAUUAUUAUUUUUUUACAGAUCUUUCUAUAAAAAAUAAACAUCUUUUGAUUGCUUGGAUUUAGGAAUUCAAUUUUUGUUUCAGUGACCAAUGUCAAGUUGCAGGCUUUGUGUGUUGCAUAUUUAAUAUUUCUACUACCACCGUAUGUCAACUGGGUAAAGCCUUCCAGAGCUCUCUAAAUACCUGAAAGACUUAAGCCUUUUUUUAAGUAAUUAAUACUUAAAAAAAAAGAUCCUGGCAUCUAUUUAUGCAACUAAAUACUUUUCAGAAAUGGUAUAUAAAAGGCUACAGUUUAAUAUCUGUAUUUUUAUAAAAGUAUGAUGAAGGGUUUGGGGUGUUUUUAUUUGUAGCAGAGGUAAGAAUAUGUAUUCAUAUAAUCUGCCUACUUUUGAGUUCUCAUAUUAACAUUUAGAUAACAUAUGAAGUAUGGCCCCCUUGGAUCCUUGUUUUUAAGUUACUUUCGAUGUGUAUACGAACAAAGACCAGGGAGAAACAGAACUUUUAAAACUAUAGGCUGCUGUGUUGGGGCCAGAAAUAAGGUGACAAGUAAAGACUUUUAUAAUACCUACCUUCAAAAUUAGAAUCAGCAGCACUGUACAAAUAAAGUGCCUGUGCUUCACCUCACACCAAGAAUCUUGCCUAACCCUGUCAGAGUGCCUAAUAUCCUGUGGUGAUUAUGUAUAAUGAAACAGUCUUAUUUUGUGCUCUUUGGUUUCUUAAAAGGAAAGCUUGUUUUCUUUCCUUUAUCAUUACAGAGGUAUGUCUUUGGUUCUUAAACUAUCUGUCUAAAAUAAAGCUGUAAAAAAUUAA